UUGCCUUUUUUUUUUUUUUUUUUUUUUUAAACUCUUGUAAACCAGGUUGAUCCAUAAACCCUGGGCCCCUUUCAGCUUUCGUCCAACCCUCUUGUCUAGAGAGCUGCCAUGUUGCCAAGCUUCAUUUCUGUAAGAAGCCUUUGUUCCUUCCCGGGGCUCAGCUCUCCCUACGCCUUUUUGUCUUGAUUAGCCACUUGGUGGCUUCUGGUACUGCCUAGAUUAGAGCUGAGGAAGGGGAGAUGUUGCUUUUGUCAGUUUUGUCAGCAGGAUGGCUUGGGAGAACAGUGUAUGUGUGGUUGUGACCAAGUAGAAAGAACUUGUUGACCAGCAGUCAGCAGUGUCCGUCAGGGAGAGCUGGCUGCAGCUUUCUUUUUUUCUUUUUUUUUUUUUGAGACGGAGUUUCACUCUUGUUGCCCAGGCUGGAGUGUAGUGGCGUGAUCUUGGCUCACUGCAACCUCCGCCUCCCAGGUUCAAGUGAUUCUCCUGCCUCAGCCUCCCGAGUAGCUGGGUUUACAGGCGUGUUCUUCCAAGCCCGACUAAUUUUGUAUUUUGAGUAGAUAUGGAGUUUCUCCAUGUUGGUCAGGCUGGUCUUGAACUCCCGACCUCAGGUGAUCCGCCCACCUCGGCCUCCCAAAGUGCUGGGAUUACAGACGUGAGCCACCGCGCCCGGCCCUGGCUGUAGCUUUCUUAUAGAGAACAUGCUUCCCACUUAGCAUUCCAGCCAGUUAGGGCUUUCCGUGGAGAGAUGCCCUCAUGCUAGCUGGUUUUUAAAACCAACAGCUGCUUCUUCCUUUGUGCCUGUUCCUCAUGUCAAGGGCUUUAUCCCUAUUAUUUCAUUUAACCUUCACAGCCCUUGAGAUAGGUGCUGCUGUUAUCCCAUUCAGUAGAUCAGAAAAGCAAGGCUCAGGUUACAGACUAAGAGCAUACUCCAGAGAAGAGGUGGAGCUGGUUGAGUUACUUGGUCUGCAGAAAGGAGCAUGAGGCCCGAAUCUGUAGGCUGCUGGAUGAGGCAGUAUGAAAUAUCUCCUUUGAAAUAUCAUGUCUACUUUGGACAUGAAAUAUCUUUUGUUUUGUUUUGUUUUUUGAAACCGAGUCUCUAGCUCUGUCACCCAGACUGAAGUGCAGUGGCGCGAUCUUGGCUCACUGCAAUCUCCGCCUCCCAGGUUCAAGCGAUUCUCCUACCUCAGCCUCCUGAGUAGCUGGGGCUACAGGCACCCACCACUUCACUGGUCUAAUUUUUGCAUUCUUAGUAGAGACGGAGUUUCGCCAUGUUGGCAAGGCUAGUCUCAAACUCCUGACCUCAGGUGAUCUGCCUGCCUUGGCCUCCCAAAGUGCUGGGAUUAGUUUUUUUUUUUUUUUUUUUGAGACACAGUUUCACUCUGUCUCGCAAGCUGGAGUGCAAUGGCACAAUCUUGGCUUACUGCAAUCUCUGCCUCCCAGGUUCAAGUUCUUGUGCCUCAGCCUCCUGAGUAGCUGGAAUUUCAGGCACCCACCAUCGCGCCCAGCUAAUUUUUGUAUUACUGGUAGAGACAAGGUUUUGCCGUGUUGGCCAGGCUGGUCCCGAACUCCUGACCUCAAGUGAUCUGCCUGCUUUGGCUUCCCGAAGGCAUGAGCCACCACACCCGGUCUGAACAUGAAAUGUCUUUACCAAGCACUGUUUUUGCCAAGUCCGUGGUGUGUGCUGAACCCAGCAUCCUUGUGGGCCCUGUGGAGUUGGCCUGUUCCUUAGAGUGGGCGUCCAGAUCUGUUCUUUGACCAGGGGGAGGAGCAGCCAGUGCUGAAAAUGGGAACCGAAAUACCCGGGAGCUUUGUCCGGGAGGUACGGGGCAGGACUGGCUCAAGGCAAGGCGUUGGCCUCUUCCCAUUUCCUCAUGGGGGCCAGUUCCAAGUCGGUCUCCCAGGGUGGUUGCUUUCUUGUUCCCGAGGGCUCUGGGCAGCGGACCGAGUGCAGCCAUGUCAGGCGUUGCCAAUCCAGGCUCUGGGAAUAGAGUGCUCCCUGCACAGGCCGCCACGGCAGGCUUUUCUCCUGCUUGCUUGUCUCAAGAGAGUUUGGCAGGUCUAGAUUGAAAUGAUUAGCGCGGUGGGGCUUCCCCCACUUUUCUUGGGGGAUUAUGUCGAGGUCUAUUAAGCAUGUUCCCUUGGCAUUUAAUCCCACUCUGACACGGAUUUUGCCGGCAGUCUGUUAAGUGGCAUCGCUGAAACCUGGUUGCUGUUUUGUUGAGACCGCCUUUGUGCCGUCGCGCUGGUGGCCCACGGGAUUCCCAUUUGGCUCGACUUCCUUUCUUUUUGCUUUCUGUUGAACAGAGUCUGAAGAAUAUAGUCAAGACCUCGUGUUCACGCAGGACGUUUAGCUAGGAGAGCAUCUUGGGUGUCGUGAGGGGGGACCCCUUGAGGUGACUGUGGACAGAAGUUAGCCCAGGGCUCGGAGGGGCUUGAGGGCCUGACAUGGCCAGAGGGCCCUGAGAAUGCAGUGAUCUGUUUAUUGUUGCUGUCUCAGUGCCCCUUUAUCAACCGUCAGCAGUUUAACAACAACAAAAAAAUCCUAUGUAUUUCUCUGCCUCUCUCAACUUUAGGGAAACAAAAUUUCAAGUAGUCACUGCCUGUUUUGUGAAAAGUUGUAUGGUUGAUUCUCUUUGAGCCCAGAUGUGCCUGGAGCUGUUAAUAUCGAUAAUGUGCAGAAUCCCUCUUUGGCUCAGGUCUUUGUAGGGUGAAUUUGAAUGCUGCACUUCUCUACCUUGGUGAUUCCUUUCUAGAAUCAUUCUGGAUGAUGGUUAAGGCUCUUGGAGUUCCUUGAAUGGUCUUUUGUCCUCUGCCCGCAGGUGUUAGAUGUAGAGUAGCCUGUACCUUCGUCCGAGCCAGCGAGUGGCAUCAGGACAGGGAAGGAGGCCUCAGCUGACCCUGGGCAAGACUGUCGCCUGCUGUGCCGCGGUGUUGGACAUAAGGGAGGGCGUGCUGAGGCUGCCACCCACUCCGGCUCAGCUGACCCAGCCCUGAUGAUCAGGCACCUGCCUUGUGGACCAAGUUUCUUGUCAGUGCAGAAAAGGAGGGAAGAUGGAGAGUUGGAAGAAGGUGAAUUGGAAGAUGAUGGGGCAGAGGAGACCCAGGAUACCUCCGGAGGGCCUGAGAGAAGCCGGAAAGAAAAGGGGGAGAAGCAUCACAGUGAUUCGGAUGAGGAGAAGUCCCACAGGAGACUGAAGCGGAAACGGAAGAAAGAGCGGGAGAAAGAGAAAAGGAGGUCGAAGAAGAGGAGGAAAUCCAAGCACAAACGCCAUGCUUCUUCUAGCGAUGACUUCUCUGACUUCUCAGAUGACUCGGAUUUCAGCCCCAGUGAGAAAGGUCACCGCAAGUACAGAGAGUACAGCCCCCCAUAUGCGCCGUCCCACCAGCAGUACCCCCCAUCGCAUGCCACGCCCCUGCCCAAGAAGGCAUACUCCAAGAUGGACAGCAAGAGUUAUGGCAUGUACGAGGACUACGAGAAUGAGCAGUAUGGGGAAUAUGAGGGCGACGAGGAGGAGGACAUGGGCAAGGAGGACUAUGACGACUUCACCAAAGAGCUGAACCAGUACCGGCGUGCCAAGGAGGGCAGCAGCCGCGGCCGAGGCAGCCGAGGCCGGGGCCGGGGCUACAGGGGCCGAGGAAGCCGUGGAGGAUCGCGAGGCCGCGGCAUGGGCAGGGGCAGCCGAGGCAGGGGCAGAGGCUCUAUGGGAGGAGACCACCCGGAGGAUGAAGAGGAUUUCUACGAGGAAGAGAUGGACUAUGGAGAGAGUGAGGAGCCAAUGGGAGACGACGACUAUGACGAGUACUCCAAGGAGCUGAACCAGUACCGCCGCUCCAAGGACAGCCGAGGCCGAGGGCUAAGUCGAGGCCGUGGCAGGGGCUCCCGAGGUCGAGGGAAAGGAAUGGGUCGGGGCCGAGGCCGAGGUGGCAGCCGAGGAGGGAUGAACAAGGGCGGAAUGAACGAUGACGAAGACUUCUAUGACGAGGACAUGGGCGACGGUGGUGGUGGAAGCUACCGGAGUCGUGACCAUGACAAGCCCCACCAGCAGUCGGACAAGAAAGGCAAAGUCAUUUGCAAGUACUUCGUGGAAGGGCGCUGCACCUGGGGAGACCACUGUAAUUUUAGCCAUGACAUCGAACUCCCAAAGAAGCGAGAACUGUGCAAGUUUUACAUCACUGGAUUUUGCGCCAGAGCUGAGAACUGCCCUUAUAUGCACGGUGAUUUCCCGUGUAAGCUGUACCACACCACUGGGAACUGCAUCAAUGGUGACGACUGCAUGUUUUCCCACGACCCUCUGACCGAAGAGACGAGGGAGCUCUUGGAUAAGAUGUUGGCCGAUGAUGCAGAAGCAGGUGCCGAGGAUGAGAAGGAGGUGGAGGAACUGAAGAAGCAGGGCAUCAACCCCCUGCCCAAACCGCCCCCUGGUGUGGGCCUCCUGCCCACCCCUCCUCGGCCCCCUGGCCCGCAGGCUCCAACCUCUCCCAACGGCAGGCCCAUGCAGGGUGGCCCCCCGCCCCCGCCCCCUCCCCCUCCCCCACCGCCCGGGCCCCCUCAGAUGCCCAUGCCGGUGCAUGAGCCACUGUCCCCGCAGCAGCUGCAGCAGCAGGACAUGUACAACAAGAAGAUCCCCUCCUUGUUUGAGAUCGUGGUGCGGCCCACGGGACAGCUGGCUGAGAAGCUGGGUGUGAGGUUCCCUGGACCCGGUGGACCCCCAGGGCCAAUGGGCCCUGGGCCCAACAUGGGACCCCCAGGGCCAAUGGGCGGUCCAAUGCAUCCUGACAUGCACCCCGACAUGCACCCGGACAUGCACCCUGACAUGCACGCAGACAUGCACGCAGACAUGCCGAUGGGCCCUGGCAUGAAUCCUGGCCCACCCAUGGGCCCUGGCGGCCCUCCAAUGAUGCCCUACGGCCCUGGAGACUCCCCACAUUCUGGAAUGAUGCCCCCUAUCCCGCCAGCCCAGAACUUCUAUGAAAACUUCUACCAGCAGCAGGAGGGCAUGGAGAUGGAGCCCGGACUCCUGGGGGAUGCAGAGGACUACGGGCACUACGAAGAGCUGCCAGGGGAGCCUGGGGAGCACCUCUUCCCUGAGCACCCUCUGGAGCCCGACAGCUUCUCUGAGGGAGGGCCCCCAGGCCGGCCGAAGCCAGGCGCCGGUGUCCCUGACUUCCUGCCCUCAGCCCAGAGGGCCCUGUACCUGAGGAUCCAGCAGAAGCAGCAGGAGGAGGAGGAGAGAGCGAGGAGGCUGGCUGAGAGCAGCAAGCAGGACCGGGAGAAUGAGGAAGGUGACACCGGAAACUGGUACUCAAGUGAUGAGGAUGAGGGUGGAAGCAGUGUCACCUCCAUCCUGAAGACCUUGAGGCAGCAGACGUCCAGCCGACCCCCGGCUUCAGUUGGGGAGCUGAGCAGCAGUGGGCUGGGGGACCCCCGCCUCCAGAAGGGACACCCCACAGGAAGCCGGCUGGCUGACCCUCGCCUCAGCCGGGACCCCAGACUCACCCGCCAUGUGGAGGCUUCUGGCGGGUCUGGCCCAGGUGAUUCGGGACCCUCCGAUCCUCGGCUGGCUCGCGCCCUGCCCACCUCCAAGCCCGAAGGCAGCCUUCAUUCCAGCCCUGUGGGCCCCAGCAGUUCCAAGGGGUCUGGGCCGCCCCCAACGGAGGAGGAGGAAGGGGAGCGGGCCCUGCGGGAGAAGGCCGUGAACAUUCCCCUGGACCCACUCCCCGGGCACCCUCUGCGGGACCCACGGUCACAGCUGCAGCAGUUCAGCCACAUCAAGAAGGACGUGACCCUGAGCAAGCCCAGCUUCGCCCGCACCGUGCUCUGGAAUCCCGAGGACCUGAUCCCCCUACCCAUCCCCAAGCAGGACGCAGUGCCCCCCGUGCCCGCGGCCCUGCAAUCCAUGCCCACCCUGGACCCCCGGCUGCACCGCGCUGCCACGGCAGGGCCCCCCAACGCCCGGCAGCGCCCGGGCGCCUCCACGGAUUCCAGCACACAGGGCGCCAACCUCCCCGACUUUGAACUUCUGUCUCGCAUCCUCAAGACAGUCAAUGCCACCGGCUCCUCGGCCGCCCCCGGUUCCAGCGACAAACCCAGUGACCCCCGGGUGCGGAAGGCCCCCACCGACCCUCGGCUGCAGAAACCCACAGACUCUACGGCCUCCUCCCGGGCUGCCAAGCCCGGCCCUGCUGAGGCGCCCUCUCCCACCGCCAGCCCGAGUGGGGAUGCCUCCCCACCAGCCACCGCUCCCUACGACCCCCGCGUGCUGGCGGCCGGUGGACUGGGCCAGGGCGGAGGGGGCGGGCAGAGCAGUGUGCUGAGCGGUAUCAGCCUCUACGACCCGAGGACUCCCAACGCGGGGGGCAAAGCCACAGAGCCGGCUGCUGACACGGGUGCCCAGCCCAAGGGUGCUGAGGGCAAUGGCAAGAGCUCGGCCUCCAAGGCUAAGGAGCCCCCGUUCGUCCGCAAGUCUGCCCUGGAACAGCCAGAGACAGGGAAGGCCGGUGCUGAUGGGGGCACCCCCACGGACAGAUACAACAGCUACAACCGGCCCCGGCCCAAGGCUGCUGCAGCCCCCGCUGCCACCACCGCCACCCCACCCCCCGAGGGUGCCCCACCCCAGCCCGGGGUGCACAACCUGCCCGUGCCCACCCUCUUCGGGACGGUGAAGCAGACACCCAAGACGGGCUCAGGAAGCCCAUUUGCUGGGAACAGUCCGGCCCGCGAGGGUGAGCAGGAUGCGGCAUCCCUGAAGGAUGUUUUUAAAGGCUUCGACCCCACGGCCUCCCCCUUUUGCCAGUAGUGUCCAGCCAGAGCUGCGGCUCCAGCCACCCUUCCUAGGGUGGCAUUCAGGGCAGCACCCAGGGUAGGGAACUUGGGGGCAAGGGGAGGCAGGCUGGGUGUUCCUUUUUUCUUUUCUUUUUCUUUUGCUUUCCGUCUCUUUUAUUUUUUUUUAAAGUAGUACUUUCUUUGAGAUUUGUAAAUUGUAUAUAACCAUCUUAAGUUCUGGUCAGUGUGGCGGGCUCAGGGGCUCCUGCUGAGCAAACCGACUCAUGCCCGCAAACCUGUGAACUUUCGCCAGUGCCUGGCCUCAGACUCUGUGGGCUCUGCGUGGCCGGGCCUUGCUGGAGGCCCAGUGGGUUUUCUGGGCAAAGCAUGGCCCCUUUUCCCCAGGACAAAGGGAACAGUUGGUGUCUGGGAAGGUAUUGAACGCUCCUCACCCUGUGCCCGAAGAGACCCGGAACCAAGACCAUGGCAGGGCCUGCGUGGAAGCAGGUCCAGGCGUUUCUAGAACCCUAGGGUGCACCAUCACUGUCUUUUCAGUGCAGGCUGUAACAACCCACUCAGGAGACAGUGAGAGUGAAAAGGUAUUAAGGAAAAAGCCCCCAGCGGCACUAUGGGGGCUCCCUGGCGCAUGCCUGCUCCUGUCCCUGGAUUACCACACGUGCCCUCCCUGCCACCCUCCGUCUAGAGCAAGCGGAUGCCCCCCAGCCUGCAGCAGAAGCCUCCACAGUGAGAACUGGACCCAAAGGUAGUGGGGGCCGGUGUGGGGCAGAGUCCUGAAGAGCCACCUCUAGGAGGCAGCCCCUAGGAGCACGCACGUUCUGUCAGUAUUACCCCACCUGUCCUAUCAGGUGGGCCACACCCUGCUUGCCCACACCAGGGUCUGUCCUGGUCCUCAAGCCACGCACCCGCUAUGCCUGCACUGCAGCCCAGCCCCGGACAGCUCCAGGAUCCGUGCAGUGGCUGCGCCGCCAGGCCCCAACAAUGGGGACCCUGGGGUGGCUCCUGGCCAAGUGUUCUCUGUUUUCCUCGCACCUCCUUACACUGUGUGACCUGCAGGGCAUGAGGUAUUGAUGUGUUCGGGUUUCCUUUCCCAAGCCAGCAGAUGCAGGUGUUCCAAGGUGUGUUGCUCUGUGGGAUUUGUGGACACUUAAGAAACGGACUGAGUGGGAACCCUGCAGCCAGGGGAUGGGGAGCCUCUGCUCCCCCCAUGCUCCCACCCUGGCUGAGGGCCAGCCUCAUCUGCAGAGCCCUGGAGGAGGCCCACCUAUGGACACAGCCCGAGAGAUGGGCGCAAGGGGUGCUGGGGGAGGCCUGCUAUCCUGCCUCUGGGCCACUUGAGGGGCCUCAGGAAGUGUGUGCUUGUGGCUGCAUCUGCCCGUCUCCCUGGCCCACCAUGUGGCUGCAGGCCAAGCUCUUCAUUGCUGACCAUGAAGAGACCUAGUUACCUGCCAAGGGAUUCCCCUUCCCUCCUCCUCAGGGUGGGGUGAACAAGGCUCCUAUCCCACCCCACCCCAAAAAGAGAAAAAUGAAAAACUCAUAGUUUGGAGCCAGGAGGCAGGGUGUCCUACAGGGCUGCACAGCCCUGAGGGGUCAGUGCUGGGAUCUGGUUGGUUGGUUUGUCUUUUUGUCUUUUUUUUUUUUUUUUUUUUUACACAAUCAUUAAUGAGAUUUGUCUUCAGCCACCAGUGUUGGCCUUGAAGCAGAGGGCACAGCCCUUGGUGUUUGUAAAAUAAGUAUGAAUACACAGUGUGGCAGUGUUGUGGUUUUUGUUGUUGUUUUUCCUCUCCUUUUGAGAAUUUUCUUUUGUAAAAGAAAAAUAUUUUUUAAACCGAAAUCUGUGGAUGAAAUAGAAGCUGGAGCCCUCCUCUUGGAAUAUUCAGCCUAAGAACCUCAUAGGACUAUGAAUUCACCCGAAAUUCUCAUUUGCCAUCAGGCCGAGCUUUUAAAGAAAAAUUGUUCUCUAACCAGGAUUGUAACAAAAGUGUAAAUACUGUUUCAGAGUUGAGAGUUGGUGGUGCAAAUAUGUAUAUAAUGAACUGUAUUUUUACAAUGAUCGCCGCAUGACUAUUUCACACCCUUUUUAUACUCCAUAUCUGUCUUCCAGAAACGUCACCUGCCUUUCUCCUGUGGUCUCUUAAUCCAGUAAUUGUAUUACUGCCAUUAAAGGAUGCAGUUAUUUUAAAAA